AUGGAUAAAGAAAACAGCUCAAUGGUGACUGAGUUUAUCUUCAUGGGCAUCACCCAGGACCCUCAGAUGGAGAUCAUCUUCUUCGUGGUCUUCCUCAUAGUUUACCUGGUUAAUGUAGUGGGGAAUAUUGGUAUGAUUAUCCUGAUUACAACAGACACUCAGCUUCACACACCCAUGUAUUUUUUCCUCUGCAACCUCUCCUUUGUUGACCUGGGCUACUCCUCAGCCAUUGCCCCCAGGAUGCUGGCUGACUUCCUAACAAAUCACAAAGUUAUCUCCUUCUCCAGCUGUGCCACCCAGUUUGCUUUUUUUGUAGGUUUUGUGGAUGCUGAGUGCUAUGUCCUGGCAGCCAUGGCCUAUGGUCGUUUUGUGGCCAUUUGUCGACCCCUCCACUAUAGCACCUUCAUGUCCAAGCAGGUCUGCUUGGCUCUCAUGCUGGGCUCUUACCUGGCUGGUCUAGUGAGUUUAGUAGCCCACACUACCCUCACCUUCAGCCUGAGUUACUGUGGUUCCAAUAUCAUCAAUCAUUUCUUCUGCGAAAUCCCACCACUCUUGGCCCUCUCUUGCUCAGACACCUACAUCAGUGAGAUCUUGCUCUUCAGUCUGUGUGGCUUCAUUGAAUUCAGCACCAUCCUCAUCAUCUUCAUCUCCUAUACCUUUAUCCUUGUUGCAAUCAUCAGAAUGCGUUCAGCUGAAGGCCGCCUUAAGGCUUUCUCCACCUGCGGGUCUCACCUUACUGGCAUCACCCUCUUCUAUGGCACAGUCAUGUUUAUGUACCUGAGGCCAACAUCCAGCUACUCCCUGGACCAAGACAAGUGGGCCUCUGUGUUCUACACGGUUAUCAUCCCCAUGUUAAAUCCCUUGAUCUACAGUUUGCGGAACAAGGAUGUGAAAGCUGCUUUCAAAAAGCUAAUUGGAAAAAAAUCUCAAUAA